AGUUCCUCUCCCGCCGCGCCGGGCCGCGCUGCCGCUCGCUCCCCGGCCGUGGCGCCUCCGGGCCAGACGCGCUGCAGCCUCCAGCCCGCGGCAAGCGGGGCGGCCGCGCCACCCCCGGCCCCGCGCCAGCAGCCCCUCGCCGCGCGUCCAGCGUUCCCGGCCAGCAGCCUCCCCAUACGCAGGUCCUGCUGGGCCGCCCCGUCGCGCCCCCCACUCUGAACUCAAGUCACCGUGGAGCUCCGCCGCCCCGAAACUUUCACCGCGAGCGGGAAAUAUGGGAUGUAUAAAAUCAAAAGGGAAAGACAGCUUGAGUGACGAUGGAGUAGAUUUGAAGACUCAACCAGUACGUAAUACUGAAAGAACUAUUUAUGUGAGAGAUCCAACGUCCAAUAAACAGCAAAGGCCAGUUCCAGAAUCUCAGCUUUUACCUGGACAGAGGUUUCAAACUAAAGAUCCAGAGGAACAAGGAGACAUUGUGGUAGCCUUGUACCCCUAUGAUGGCAUCCACCCGGACGACUUGUCUUUCAAGAAAGGAGAGAAGAUGAAAGUCCUGGAGGAGCAUGGAGAAUGGUGGAAAGCAAAGUCCCUUUUAACAAAAAAAGAAGGCUUCAUCCCCAGCAACUAUGUGGCCAAACUCAACACCUUAGAAACAGAAGAGUGGUUUUUCAAGGAUAUAACCAGGAAGGACGCAGAAAGGCAGCUUUUGGCACCAGGAAAUAGCGCUGGAGCUUUCCUUAUUAGAGAAAGUGAAACAUUAAAAGGAAGCUUCUCUCUGUCUGUCAGAGACUUUGACCCUGUGCAUGGUGAUGUUAUUAAGCACUACAAAAUUAGAAGUCUGGAUAAUGGGGGCUAUUACAUCUCUCCACGAAUCACUUUUCCCUGUAUCAGCGACAUGAUUAAACAUUACCAAAAGCAGGCAGAUGGCUUGUGCAGAAGAUUGGAGAAGGCUUGUAUUAGUCCCAAGCCACAGAAGCCAUGGGAUAAAGAUGCCUGGGAGAUCCCCCGGGAGUCCAUCAAGUUGGUGAAAAGGCUUGGCGCUGGGCAGUUUGGGGAAGUCUGGAUGGGUUACUAUAACAACAGUACCAAGGUGGCUGUGAAAACCCUGAAGCCAGGAACUAUGUCUGUGCAAGCCUUCCUGGAAGAAGCCAACCUCAUGAAGACCCUGCAGCAUGACAAGCUCGUGAGGCUCUACGCUGUGGUCACCAGGGAGGAGCCCAUUUACAUCAUCACCGAGUACAUGGCCAAGGGCAGUUUGCUGGAUUUCCUGAAGAGCGAUGAAGGUGGCAAAGUGCUGCUUCCAAAGCUCAUUGACUUUUCUGCUCAGAUUGCAGAGGGAAUGGCAUACAUCGAGCGGAAGAACUACAUUCACCGGGACCUGCGAGCAGCUAAUGUUCUGGUCUCCGAGUCACUCAUGUGCAAAAUUGCAGAUUUUGGCCUUGCUAGAGUAAUUGAAGAUAAUGAGUACACAGCAAGGGAAGGUGCUAAGUUCCCUAUUAAGUGGACGGCUCCAGAAGCAAUCAACUUUGGAUGUUUCACUAUUAAGUCUGAUGUGUGGUCCUUUGGAAUCCUCCUAUACGAAAUUGUCACCUAUGGGAAAAUUCCCUACCCAGGGAGAACUAAUGCCGACGUGAUGACCGCCCUGUCCCAGGGCUACAGGAUGCCCCGUGUGGAGAACUGCCCAGAUGAGCUCUAUGACAUUAUGAAAAUGUGCUGGAAAGAAAAGGCAGAAGAGAGACCAACGUUUGACUACUUACAGAGCGUCCUGGAUGAUUUCUACACAGCCACGGAAGGGCAAUACCAGCAGCAGCCUUAGAGCACAGGGAGACCCGUCCAUUUGGCAGGGGUGGCUGCCUCAUUUAGAGAGGAAAAGUAACCAUCACUGGUUGCACUUAUGAUUUCAUGUGCGGGGAUCAUCUGCCGUGCCUGGAUCCUGAAAUAGAGGCUAAAUUACUCAGGAAGAACACCCUCUAAAUGGGAAAGUAUUCUGUACUCUUAGAUGGAUUCUCCACUCAGUUGCAACUUGGACUUGUCCUCAGCAGCUGGUAAUCUUGCUCUGCUUGACAACAUCUGAGUGCAGCCGUUUGAGAAGAAAACAUCUAUUCUCUCCAAAAAUGCACCCAACUAGCUCUAUGUUUACAAAUGGACAUAGGACUCAAAGUUUCAGAGACCAUUGCAAUGAAUCCCCAAUAAUUGCAGAACUAAACUCAUUUAUAAAGCUAAAAUAACCGGAUAUAUACAUAGCAUGACAUUUCUUUGUGCUUUGGCUUACUUGUUUAAAAAAAAAAAAAAACUAAUCCAACCUGUUAGAUUUUGCAGGUGAAGUCAGCAGCUUAAAAAUGUCUUUCCCAGAUUUCAAUGAUUUUUUUCCCCCUACCUCCCAAAAUCUGAGACUGUUAAAACAUUUUUCUUCUAUGAACACUGCUCAGACCUGCUAGACAUGCCAUAGGAGUGGCGUGCACAUCUCUCUCUCUUCCAGCAGGAGGAGCCCGUGAGCACGCACAGCUGCCCUGUCUGCUCACCCGAAGGCACCGGGCUCACCUGGACCUCCCAGGAAAGGGAGAAGAGCCUCAGAAACUGCUCUGUGUUUAGAAGGAAUAUUUUUAAGAGUCCAGCUUUUUCAUUUCCACAAUUUCCUAUAUCCAGAUUUGUUUUGACAAUGUAGUUUGGAAGAACUAAGAUUCUAAUCUCUGAAGAACCUUAUAGGGCCUUCUAAAACAUAAGAGUUUCCUUUGUUGCUUCAAAUAUUUGAACAUUAUGUUAAAGAUCAAGUAUUAAUUUUAGUUGUACUCUAGAAAGCUAAAGUGCCACAUUCGGGGCUAUUUUUAUGAUUCAGCAAUCUUUUCUAAAUUGUGUAGCAUGUGUAUGAGACUAUUUAUACCCAAGGAUAUGAAGGAACAUAAGUGACUACAAGGCUCUAAUAAGCCACGGUGGCAGGAGGUUCAAGCGGUUCUGUUCACUAAAUUUUUCUCCUGUAAGCUUUGAAUGGAAACUUCUGUAUCACAUGAUGUGUUUCACUUAUGCUGUUGUGUAUAUACCUAAUAUUUCUAUUUUUGAUUUUAUUUUAAUACACCUCGUCCAAUAACAUCUCAAGCUUUUUAUUUGCAUUUACAUUUUCAGCUGUGGUCAGUGUAAAAAUUGGUCAUCAGCUGGGGGCGGGGUGGUUAGAAGUGAUUCAACAGAGCUACAUGCUUUAAACUUGCCCAAGUUCUACCUCCUUCCUUUGAACAUUUCAGAUUGGAGAACCAAGGAGUUGAUUGCCUGAACACCUGAACAUCCGUUUAUGGGGGCCAGAUAGAAUUUGUUUUCAAAUAGGCUUAACAGGCAUCAUUAAAAUUUCAUUCUGUGUGUUUUGUUUAGGCUUGAGGUGCUUAGAAGAUGGGAUAAAAUAUUCUACUUUUUUCUAAAUUUUAACUUUGUUUCCUAUGUGAUUUUUUUAAAUGUCCUUUCUAAAAUAUUCUAAAAUUAUUGAUUCACAAGUGCCAUGUUCAGAACUAUAGAAUAUUACUGUUACAUAAUGUCUGCACAGCUGGUCCCUUGAUUCAGUGGUAAGGUUUUUGUGUACACCCCCCUGCUUGCAUUUUAUUUCAGAACCACAAGUAUUACCCAAUAUGUUACAUGGAGAGGAACUAUAAAGAAUCCCUAAGGCAAAAAGAAGUCUCUAGAAAAUGACUAGAGGUUUUUUUUUUAGCAUAACAAAUUUAUUUAAAGAAAAUUAUUAAAUUUAUCUUCGCCUUGUUUUGCUUCUCCCAGUUCCUCCUCUUCUUGCCAUUUUCCACUUGUCUUUCCCUCCCAAUCAAGCCUGUGAUCCUUACCUCCAUGUGGGCCCUUCACCAGCUUGGGCCUCAUCUCUGGUGUCCAGCAUGUGUGGAAGUCACACGUUCCCUUGAUGAACAGCACACACAGUCUCCUUACUUAGCUAUAGGUUUCCAGCCUCCCUGUGACAGACAGGCAUAAUGAGGGGCUGAAUAGGUGUUUGUAGCAUUUUCGGGUAUCCAGUGGUGUGCAAAAUGGCUCAUGUCAUCACACCUCAGGUUAUUGUAGAGAACUGGAAAGACAGAAUCCAUACUCCCUACCGCCAAGAUUCUGACUUAGCUGUUGUGCAGCGGGAGAUGUAUGUCAGUCUAUUUUAAAAGCUUCUCCAGUCAGCUAGACACAGUGGCUCAUGCCUGUAAUCUCAGCACUUUGGGAGGCUAAGGCAGGAGGAUCGCUUGAGCUCAGGAGUUAGACACCAGCCUGAGCAAUAUAGCAAGUCUCUACAAAAAAUUUUAAAAAUUAGCUAAGUGUGGUGGCACAUACCUAUGGUCCCAGCUACUCAGGAGGCUGAGGUGGGAGGAUUGCUUGAGCCCAGGAAGUCAAGGCUGCAGUGAGCUAUGAUCGUGCCACUGCACUCCAGCCUGGGCAAGAGUGAGACCCUGUCUCAAAAAAAAAAACCAAAAAAACAAAAAAACCCUUCCCUGGUGAAUAUAAUGUAUGCUCAGUCUUGAGAGUCACCAUUUGGUUUGACCCAUAUUACAAAGCCCAGCCUUCUUUUUCCUCAGAUGGUUUCAUUUCUCAAAGGGGAGUGGAAGAGAAGGAAGGAGGAAAAAAACGUGCCUUCCUUCCUGGUGAACAUGAAGCUCACUGAACCUAAAGGAGACUCACAGGCUAGAAACCAGUGUCCUUAGUAGUAGGGGCCACCUGGGGCUUCCGUGGCUUCUCCAGGCAUACCUCCUGAGGUUCCACAGAAUCCCCUUGCAGAAAGUACUUCUGAUGAGCCACUGGGAACGUGUACUGUCCAAGCCCCCUUCUAGGGGAAAUUCACUGCCACAGAAGCCAGCAGCCCUGGCUGUCCCAAGGGUGCAUAAAAGGAUAAUAACUAAAAGGAGGGAAUUAAUUUUGUUGCCUACACCAGGGAUAGAUCGAGGGCACUGAAAGCAUCAUAAGUAUAAACUCAUCUCCACGUCAGCUUGUGGAGUCUGCUUUCUCGCUCUCUCUUUUUUUUUUUUUUUUGACAGAGUCUCACUCUGUCACGCAGGCUAGAGUUGCAGUGGUGCGAUCUCAGCUCAUUGCAACCUCCCCCUCUCUGGUUGGAGCGAUUCUUCUCCUGCCUCAGCCUCCCUAGUAGCUGGAACUACAGGCACACACCAUCUCGCCUGGCUAAUUUUUGUAUUUUUAGUAGAGAUGGGGUUUCACCAUGUUAGCCAGGCUGGUCUCGAACUCCUGACCUCAGGCGAUCCGCCUGCCUCGGCUUCCCAAAGUGCUGGGAUUACAAGUGUGAGCCACUGUGCCCGGUCGGGGUCUGCUUUCUCUUUAUUCCCCGUCCUCUCACAAACUACAUCCAGGGGCGGUAGCUGCUAAAAGGACUCAAUUCUGCAACCUCAGCUUCUGACACCUUCAAAUAAAUUAAAUGCUGGUCCUAGGGCUCGCUCCCCAGCUCUUCUGAUGUCACUGCCAGGUUCCACAGCCAGUUGUCGGACAUCUCCUGCUUCCUCAGCCAAGAACACCUCUCAGAUGAGAUCAAACCGCCCAGCUUUCCUCUUAGCAUCUUCCUUUAUUUUCCACUUCUGGCUGGUGGAAGAGAGAUCGUAGUUCUCUAUUCCCUACAUUUUAACUCCACGAAUAUUUUAGAUUAAGUGAAGUCUUGCUGUUCUUCCUGAUGGAAAUGGUAAUUAUAAACAUACAAAGAUACCCAUACACACAUUCUUUACUCAGGGCCCUCUUGUGCUUUGGCAAAUGAUAAAAAUUAUCUCUAACUCACACAACGACCCUGGAAGAUCUGGACAAUGCUAUCACUAUUUCACAGCUGAGAGAUCGGGAGCAUUUAAAGCCACAGAAGGAAUAGAUUGGCUUCGCUUCAUAUUGUUUCCUUGUGAAAUAAAACCAGUGAAACACC